GGUAACGUGCUGCGGUCGCAUUCCGCGCUGCUGAAGGUUUGUCCUUUUGAUGUUUGGAAUGCGUUCUUAUUACUGCUCACUCUUUGGGUCUGCACUGUCUAUAUGAGCUGCAACACACACCUCGAAGGUCUGCAGCUUCACUCCUGAAGCUAGCGAGACCACGAACUCACCAGGAGGAACGAACAACUCUAGAUGCGCCCCCUUAAGAGCUGUAACACUCGCCGCGAAGGUCUGCAGCUUCACUCCUGAGUCAGCGAGACUACGAACCCACCAGAAGGAAGAAACUCCGAACACAUCCAAACAUCAGAAGGAACAAACUCCAGACACACCGCCUUUAAGAACUGUUACGCUCACCGCGAGGGUCCACGGCUUCAUUCUCCAAGUCAGACCAAGAACCCACCAAUUCCGGACACAAAAGGUGUUCCCACCAUUCCUGUCCUCUUACUUCUCUCGCCUUACAAGCGUAGCGUGCCUCCUGUGAUUGUUGAAGAGCUGUGGUGUGCUGCUGAGUGGCGUGUGUAUUCCAUGUGAGGGGAAGGGUCCAACAGUCCUGGUCAUUCAGACUGCAGUUCCCCAGGACAGACCCACGAAGUCAAGCAUGCGGAGUGCAGCCAAGCCCUGGAACCCAGCCAUCAGAGCAGGGGGCCACGGCCCAGACCGGGUGCGGCCUCUGCCUGCAGCCUCUUCCGGCAUGAAGAGUUCUAAGUCUUCAACUUCCUUGGCUUUUGAGUCCCGACUCAGCAGGCUCAAGAGGGCCAGCAGUGAGGACACGCUCAACAAGCCAGGAAGUACCGCUGCAUCGGGGGUGGUUCGCCUGAAGAAGACCGCCACUGCCGGAGCCAUCUCGGAGCUCACGGAGAGCCGCCUGAGGAGCGGCACAGGGGCCUUUACAACAACUAAACGGACAGGCAUUCCAGCCCCACGGGAAUUUUCAGUAACUGUCUCAAGAGAGAGGUCUGUGCCACGUGGUCCCUCCAACCCCAGGAAAUCAGUGUCCAGUCCAACUUCUUCCAACACUCCCACUCCUACGAAACACCUGAGGACCCCUUCCACAAAGCCCAAGCAAGAGAAUGAAGGUGGAGAAAAGGCUGCGCUUGAGUCCCAAGUUCGGGAACUUUUGGCAGAAGCCAAAGCAAAAGAUAGUGAAAUUAACAGGCUUCGAAGUGAACUAAAGAAAUACAAAGAGAAAAGGACUCUGAACGCUGAGGGGACUGAUGCUUUGGGCCCAAAUGUCGAUGGAACAUCAGUCUCCCCAGGUGACACGGAACCUAUGAUAAGAGCUCUUGAGGAGAAGAACAAGAACUUUCAGAAAGAGCUUUCCGAUCUAGAGGAAGAAAACCGGGUCCUGAAGGAGAAACUGAUCUAUCUUGAGCACUCCCCAAAUUCAGAAGGGGCAGCAAGUCACACUGGCGACAGCAGCUGCCCAACAUCCAUAACUCAAGAGUCAAGCUUCGGAAGCCCAACUGGAAAUCAGAUGUCCAGUGACAUUGAUGAGUAUAAAAAAAACAUACAUGGAAAUGCAUUACGGACAUCAGGCUCCUCAAGUAGCGAUGUUACCAAAGCUUCUUUGUCGCCAGAUGCUUCCGACUUUGAGCACAUUACAGCAGAGACACCCUCAAGGCCCCUGUCCUCCACCAGUAACCCCUUUAAGAGUUCAAAGUGUUCUACUGCUGGGAGUUCCCCAAACAGCGUAAGUGAAUUGUCCCUGGCUUCCCUCACAGAGAAGAUACAAAAGAUGGAAGAAAACCACCAUAGCACUGCAGAAGAACUACAGGCUACUCUACAAGAAUUAUCAGACCAGCAACAAAUGGUACAGGAAUUGACAGCUGAAAAUGAGAAGCUGGUGGAUGAAAAGACGAUUUUAGAGACAUCCUUUCAUCAGCAUCGAGAGAGGGCAGAGCAGCUAAGUCAAGAAAAUGAGAAGCUGAUGAAUCUUUUACAAGAGCGAGUAAAGAAUGAAGAGCCCACCACUCAGGAAGGAAAAAUUAUUGAACUGGAGCAGAAGUGCACAGGUAUUCUUGAACAGGGCCGCUUUGAAAGAGAGAAGCUACUCAACAUUCAGCAGCAGUUGACCUGUAGCUUGCGGAAGGUUGAGGAAGAAAACCAAGGAGCUUUAGAAAUGAUUAAACGUCUGAAGGAAGAAAAUGAAAAACUGAAUGAGUUUCUAGAACUGGAACGGCAUAAUAAUAACAUGAUGGCCAAAACUUUGGAAGAGUGUAGAGUUACCUUGGAAGGGCUAAAAAUGGAGAAUGGAUCUUUGAAGUCUCAUUUGCAGGGUGAGAAGCAGAAAGCCACAGAGGCCAGUGCUGUGGAGCAGACGGCAGAGAGCUGCGAAGUUCAAGAAAUGUUGAAAGUAGCCCGAGCAGAGAAAGAUCUACUGGAACUGUCUUGCAAUGAGCUCAGACAAGAAUUACUAAAGGCAAACGGUGAAAUUAAACAUGUUUCCAGUCUGCUGGCCAAGGUGAGAAGAGACAGCUCUUUACUGGUGGAAAAGGAUUAUUCAUACCUGAAGGAGAUAUGUGAUCACCAAGCCGAACAGCUGAGCAGAACCAGCCUAAAGCUGCAAGAAAAAGCAUCAGAGAGUGAUGCAGAGAUCAAAGACAUGAAAGAAACCAUAUUUGAAUUGGAAGAUCAGGUGGAACAGCACCGGGCUGUCAAGUUACACAAUAAUCAACUCAUCAGUGAGCUAGAAAGUAGUGUGAUCAAGCUGGAGGAACAGAAGUCAGACCUGGAGAGGCAGCUGAAGACUCUGACCAAGCAGAUGAAGGAGGAGACCGAGGAAUGGAGGCGGUUCCAGGCGGAUCUGCAGACCGCAGUGGUGGUGGCCAAUGACAUCAAGUGUGAGGCCCAGCAGGAGCUGCGCACCGUGAAGAGGAAACUGCUGGAGGAGGAGGAGAAGAAUGCCCGGUUGCAGAAGGAGCUGGGGGAUGUGCAGGGCCACGGCAGGGUGGUCACCAGCAGAGCCGCCCCUCCACCUGUGGAUGAAGAGCCAGAGUCCUCUGAGGUCGAUGCUGCUGGUCGGUGGCCUGGUGUCUGUGUUAGCAGAACAUCUCCAACACCCCCAGAGUCGGCAACCACCGUUAAGUCACUUAUCAAGUCAUUUGACUUGGGACGCCCAGGUGGAGCUGGACAGAAUAUUUCUGUCCAUAAGACCCCCAGAAGUCCCCUAAGUGGGAUACCAGUGAGGACUGCUCCAGCAGCUGCUGUCUCUCCAAUGCAGAGGCAUUCGACUUACAGCAGUGUGCGGCCAGCCAGCAGAGGGGUGACUCAACGCUUGGACCUUCCUGACCUUCCCCUCUCAGAUAUUCUAAAGGGAAGGACUGAGACCCUGAAGCCAGACCCCCACCUCCGCAAGAGUCCCUCACUAGAGUCACUGAGCAGACCCCCGUCUCUGGGCUUUGGGGACACAAGACUGCUGAGUGCUUCCACCCGGGCAUGGAAACCACAAAGCAAACUCAGUGUGGAAAGAAAAGACCCUCUGGCAGCCUUGGCCCGGGAAUACGGUGGUUCCAAGCGCAAUGCUCUACUGAAAUGGUGCCAGAAGAAGACACAAGGUUAUGCGAACAUUGACAUCACCAAUUUCAGCAGCAGCUGGAGCGAUGGCCUGGCCUUCUGUGCUCUGCUCCACACCUACCUGCCUGCCCACAUCCCCUACCAGGAGCUGAAUAGUCAGGAGAAAAAGAGGAAUCUCUUGUUGGCAUUUGAAGCGGCUGAAAGUGUAGGCAUCAAACCCAGCCUGGAACUCAGCGAGAUGCUGUACACAGACCGGCCCGACUGGCAGAGUGUGAUGCAGUACGUGGCCCAAAUCUACAAGUACUUUGAGACGUAACCCUGGAGGGCCUGGGGCAGCCACCAUUGCCACCUACUGCAGCUUUUCCUGGAAGCGCCUGAUUACUGUCCACUGACCCUGCUCUGCCCACCACCCAGCUGCCUAGACUUCAAAGACAGGCUCAAUCCAAGUGGACCAACACCCAAAUAAGAAACAGAGUGGGUCCCACGAUGUACCUGUCUGAAAUGCAAAUGCAGCUGGACUGUAAAUUGGGGACUCUUUGAUCUCUUGUGGGAUGCUUCUAAAGAGGGCAGCCUCCCUCCUUCCAGACCAAGACCCCACACCCAGGCUUGUUUUGCUGAUUAUAUUGGGUGGCUGAACGAACACAUUAUCUGCAGAAAUUCAGACAAAGAACAUCUCCAAAUCAGUCUUUUGGUUGCUGUUGUUAAAAAUAUCCCGGCUUUGCCUUUAUGAAACCUUUGCCCUUGGCUGGGUGUGGUAGCUCGUGGCUGUAAUCCCAGCACUUUAGGAAGCCAAGGCAGUAGGAUCGUUUGAGCCCAGGAGUUCGAGGCUGCAGUGAGCUAUGAGCAUACCACUGCACUCCAGCCUGUGUGAAAGAGCCAGACCCUGUCUCAAAAAAAUGAUAAAACCCAAAACUUUGCCCUUGUGAACCCUCCCUUCCCCCCUCCCCCCCCAAAAAAAAACAACAAAACACAAAAAAUAAACAUUUGUUCCAGGGCAACCUGGAAACGUGCGUGCGCACUCAGCCUUUUGGGGAAAAAUGGGAGUUCUAGGUAACAAUGUUAACACCUGGAACUUGAUUCACUUUUAGCUCUCACCAUCCCUUAUUUGAUUUAUUGUAGCAAAAGGAAAGCCUGUGAGAAUGCAAGGGAGCCCCUGGCUGCUUUGCUGGAGUCCCUGGGAGGUGCCCCACACCUCUGCCACCAAAGUCUGUGUGCUCCUGAGCAGCUCGCGGCUUUCACAGUAGGGAAACCGCAGUCCUCGUCACCUGCGCCUUUGUCCUCCCAUUCGUUUACCCUCCCGUUCACAUCCACACAGGCUUGUACCCCACAGAACUUGACAGGAGGUCACAUGUGUGAAUGGCCUGUGUCUGCUUUACAGGGUUGAGCAGGCUGAGGGUGUGUGCCUCUGGGGAUGCUGGGCUGACAGCAAAUCCCAACAGUAUUUCGGCUCUGGACUGAUUUGGCCUUUAGUGCUUCCCCAGGCCUCUUUCAUCGGCAUGGGAAAAGCCCUUAGGGGUGGGCGGUGAGGGCACAUUUAUAACUAACAAAGAAGAAUGCAGUUGCCCCAGCAUCCUACUGGUCACCUUAAGUGGCAGCAGAGCCCUCCCCAGCGGUGCCCCAGUCCCUCAGAAGUGCUCAGUCCGGCCCGAGUGCCCAUCUGGUGGCUCUGCCGUGUUCUUCUGGGCGGAUCUGUGUGCACUACACAGCGAGUGAGGGCGUGGCUCACACAGUUGUUUGAGGGAAAUGGGUAAUGCCCAUCCCUUGCUGUUUUAAGUGCCAAAUAGCGUGUUAGCGCCCCUCCAACAAAGGAUCAUCCUUCCAGUGAGUCACCGAGAAUGACAGUGACUGCCAUUACUAUUCAAAGUACAUCUCUGAUUGCUGAUCUGAGCCACUGGUUCAGAGCCAGGUUCUAGAGGCUGCAGGUCCAGCCCCUUACCAUUCCUGGAGAGGUAGGAGCUCAGUCCCUUCCUCCAAGCCAGACCUUUGCAGAGGUGGCAACUGGGCUGCACGGGUCAGCAGAUCCCUGAUUCUCAAGCCACCUUGAGACAAGAACUCCGCCCCCCUGUUAGUGCAUCCCAGCUGCAGCUCUGCAUCAGAACCUACAGUGGACCCUUUUGAAAACACUCUUGGCUGCCCUAGUUGGUUAACUUCAGAAUGUCUGGAAUGGGACCAGAGAUGCAGUUCACAUGUUUUGUAAGUUCUUUAGGCGACUGAAGCACAGCUGCUUGGAGAACCACUGAGGGGUGGACACCUUCCCCUGGCAGCCACAAGGCAGGCAGCCUGCGGGAGCUCCUGAGCAGCUGUUGGGCGAUGGUCAUUACAUCACCCAUGCCUUUGUAUUUAAAUGAAACUCGACACAUAGAACCAAUUCAACCUGAAAGUUACUACUUCUGCUGAUUCAGGCACUUGUUUGAAGCAUUUUUUUUUUAUUAACCCUGUACUUCUUCUUUGCCCACCAUUAAAGUGGGGGAAAGUAAUAUCCCAAGUAGUUGAGUUGAGCUGUUGGUUGUUAGAUUUAAGCUGGAAUUAGUCCAGGGUUUUAUGUGGGGAGGCAGUUGCUGUCUUGGGAUACCCGGAGUGGGAGUGGGUGUUUUCUGUGAUUGGUUCUGUUUUUUAUUUUUACUUAUUUAUUUUGAGAUGGAGUUUCAUCCUUAUUGCCCAGGCUGGAGGGCAAUAGCACCGUCUCAGCUCACUGCAACCUCCGCCGCCCGUGUUUAAGCGAUUCUCCUGCCUCAGCCUCCCAUGUGGCUGGGAUUACAGGUGCCCAUCACCACACCCAGCUAAUGUUUUUGUAUUUUUAGUAAAGAGGGGGUUUCACCAUGUUGGCCCGGCUGGUCUCGAACUCCUGAUGGCAAGGUGAUCUGCCUGCCUCAGCCUCCCAAAGUGCUGGGAUUACAGGCAUGAGCCACUGAGCCCGGCUGUUUUUUUGUGUUUUUUUUGUUGUUGUUUGUUUGUUUUUUUUUUUGAGACAGAGUCUUGCUCUGUCGCCCAGGCUGGAGUGCCAGUGGCGCGAUUUCAGCUCACUCAGGAGUGAGCCACCACACCUGGCCUGUGAUUGGCUCUAUUUUGAGUGAUUACGUGUAAAUCAUCUAGAACCAGCUCUGAGCAAUGGCGUUGCGGUGUCCCUCCCUCCCCGCUGGGGCCAUACCAGCCCCUCUCCACUGGGAGCCCAAGUUGCCAAUGACUGUGGCCAAACUCCCCCAUUUUUGUCUGUAUCCUGCUCUCUUUAGGUUAAAAAGAAGGAAAGAAACAUGAAAGGCCAUGUACAAUUUAUUUUUACAACUCCAGGAGUUUCCCCGACUACCAUUUUUUUUUUUUUUAUUUGCCAGUGGUGUGCAUGUAGAAGAGGAAUGCCAUGUCCUGUCCAUAGAAAUACACAUGGUGGUCAGGCAUGGUGGCUCAUGCCUAUAAUCCCAGCACUUUGGGAGGCUGAGGUGGGAGGAUUGCUUGAGCCCAGGAGUUUGAGACCAGCCUGGGCAACAUGGCAAGACCUCUGACUCUAUAAAAAAAUUUUUUUUUUUUUUUUUUUUUGAGAGAGCGUCUCACUUCUCUGUCACCCAGGCUAGAGUAGUGUGAUCUUGGCUUAUUACAACUUCCGCCUCCCAGGUUCAAGAGAUUCUCCUGCCUUAGCCUCCUAAGUAGCUGGGAUUAUAGGCACAUGCCACCAUGCCUGGCAUAUUUUUGUAUUUUUAGUAGAAACAGUUUCACCAUGUUGGCCAGGCUGGUCUUGAACUCCUGACCUCAAGUGAUAAGCCUGCCUCAACCUCCCAAAGUGCUGGGACUACAGGGGUAAGCCACCGCGCCUGGCCCAAAAUUUUGUUUUUUAAUUAGCUGGGUACAAUGAUAGGCACCUGUAAUCUCAGCUGCUUGGGAGGCUGAGGUGGGAGCAUCACUUGAGCCCAGGAGUUUGAGGCUGCAGUAAGCUGUGUUUGUGCCACUGCACUCUGGCCUGGGCCAAAGAGCAAGACCCUGUCACACACACACACAAAAAAAAGAAAUACAGGUGGUGUUUUGGGGAAGGGAAGGUUCUGCUGGGGUCCUGGAACUGUGACUGAUGGCCUCAGGAGUCCAGGAAUAGGCCUUCUAGCACAGCAGCUAGUAGGGCUCCCCCAAGCCAUCCGCUGGCGUGUGGAGGUGCAGGACCUGGGGGAGGCAGUCCCCAACCCAGCUAGGCCAAGGGGUAGGGUUUUUAGGUCUGUUUUUAACAGAGCUCAGAGCACCAGGUGAAGGUGGAAAGUUGGCAGGAAAACAAGGUCAGCAUCUUAUUUUUUCUAUACUCAGCAGAGUGUGCCAUUCCCAGUUUCUGUCCUGAGGAUUUCAAAGACCACAACAGCCACAUUUCUUUCCAUCUUCCCUCAGCCAGUAGUCAUUUAAAAUUCUUCAGUUGUUCUGAAGAUCCUUUUUUUAAUGUAUCAUUUUUACAUGAAAGACAGCUGCAAAAUGCAAGCCCCAGUAGAGUUGGAGAGUUUUUCAAGGUGAGAAGUCGCUGUUCUCUGCAUUGAACAUGGAUUGAAUUUUCCUUGUCUGAUGGUAACCCAUGGCCCCCGCCCUGCGGGGAUAACAUUCUCAGGAGCUUCUCUUGUCCUAGCCCCUUCUCAUUUCAAAAAUAUUAGUCUUUUAUUUUCCUUUUUCAUUCAGUUUUUGUUUUACAGCUUUUGUAGAGACCAACCCAAGUAGAUGCAGGUGGGUGUUAGAUAAAAACACACAUCCCCAGGGGACAAGCCAUCCAGCGGUGAGGAAUCUCUGCCAUGUUCUCUUCCCUGCUGCCCACAAACGUUACGGAGACUCCCUUAGCCUCCCCCUCCUCUUCCCCACUGAGGGGCAGCUUGUGGAGAUGGAGGACUCGGGCCCAUAGAUGCAGACCCCCUACCAAAUCUAGCAAUAGUUCUCACCCUUCCAAAGCUCGAGUGCCAUUUUGAGAUGACCUACCAAUGACAUGCAGUAAAGGACAUAACCUCACAGCCUUUUUAGAAGCAUUUCGAAUAUCUACAGUUGCCUCAAUUCACGGGGCAUUUCACUCCUCUGAUCCAGGUUAGAAUUUUGCUAAAUCUGUAGCAUCCUGAAUAGCACACUAAUUUUUUUUUUUAGCACACUAACUUUAACUACAUUAGUUGAGUGUAGUUGAUACAUCUGUGGCCUCGUGUCUAUAAAGAGCACACUAGAUUGUACCCAGCACUUUUGGAUAUGACAUGCUAAUUAGAUGUAUUUAACUAUUCAUAGGAAAGUGUAUGAUAAAUGACUGUAAUAUUUCUAAUAAAUAUAUUUUGUUUCUAAUUA